CUGGGAGCUGCAGGACUGGUGCUUGCAGGGUUCAGGCCAGUGGCUCCUAUACCAUACCCAGCCUCGUCGACUCUGUGUUAUGGGCUUUUCUGGUGCUUAAGAUUCCUGCUCCAGGAGACGGCUGCUCUUCCCUCUCCAGGAGACGGCUGCUCUUCUUUCUCCAGGGAAGCCUCCAAACCAGAGGCAUCCCUGGCGUAUCCCAGCUGCUUCUCAGGCUGGGGGGAUCUUAGCUAUUUGUGUUUGAGUUGCUGGUGCCAGGCCCAGUGGCAUGGUAGUGAUCCAGCGUCUGUGGAUUGUUCUUGCAGAGGCAGUGGCUGGAGGUGCAGAGGGGAGGGGCCUUUCCCGCUUACCCACCUUUUGUCUAAGACACCGCAGUGCAUGGCAUACUUCUGCCCAUUGUGCUUCACAGGACUCUCACAAAUGUUGCUGUGCCCAUUUUACAGGUGAGGAAACUGAGGCUCAGAGAAGUCAUGGUAUGGCCCUCAGUGCUUUCAUUUUUUGUGUCUCACAGAUGGGGACCCUAAGACUCAGAGAUGUCAUGACUUAGGCCUCACCACACAGGGAGUUAACUGCUGGCUGGACUCUAGACCUGAUCCCUCAUGUUCAUGCUUGUGUUUGGUCAUGUUCUGUUACACAGCCUGUGCUGUUGUUUUAAAAAAUCCAUCAGUAUUUCCUGAUCUAGUUGAGUCUAAGCAGUACAAAGUACCUUUCAAUUUGGGUUUGUAUGGGGUUUUUUUUUUUCCCUUUUCUUUUUUCCAAGAGGAAAACAGAAUUCCUCUUCUGUUUGUUCUGUAGCUUUUCCUUUUCAAAGAGGCCAAAGGGAUGCAUGGACUUAGAGCAGAUUCACCAAGACAGGAUUACAUGCUCUGGGAUCACAUCUGUCUAUGUGACUUUGAGGCCAAAUUUGGACCUACUUGUGAAGUUGUCCAGCCAUGCACCUGUAGGCUGGAGGUUAGAGAGCAGGAGUGGGGUCUAGCUAGGCCUCUGGGGUGUGGUCCUGGGGGGUUUAGGAGUCUUACUUGAGAGUCAGUGCCUUUUUCUCCCUUUAAGGGAGAACAACGUUCAGACUGGCUGGGUGACAGCUGGUCAAGCAGAUCCCUGUUUAUGGCCUCCUUUCUGUUAGGGGGUGGGGCAGGGGAUUUUUUUAAAAAGAGCACAGUUCCUAGCGGCUUGUCCUGGAGGAGGGGCCUCGCUCACCUCCAGCCAGAGCCAGCUUAGUCUCCAUCUUUCCCUGAGCCUGCUCAUUUUUGCUCUUUUCCUUGUUCUCUGACUCAUUAAAGAAGGAGCAGGGGCCCAGAGCUGACCUCAUGAAUAGGGCAACAGGAAGCCAGGUUGGGGAGGAGGAGGCUGGAACUGGUGGCUGUGUCCUCUGGGGGUGCCCACUUUCCUUGCUGUCUCUGGGCUGUUCUGGGCUGAAGGAGCAGAAGGGCCUGUGGCCACUGGGCUAAGAGGAUUAAGAGGUGAUGCAGGUGGUCCCAGUGUGGGAACCUCUGACUCAGGUCCCCUUAGCAGGAGUUAUAGGGCCUGCGUUCCCCGGGGGCCUAAGGGGGCAUGUUCAGAGCAGCUGAACCUGGUUCUUGAUCUAGAUAGAGACACAUCCCUUGAACUUCUCAGACCAUCUAGAGUCAGACCUGCGUUGCUGUCCUCUUGAUUUAGCUCCCAGGACCUGGGUGUCCCAGCCAGCCUGUGGGGUGCCAGGGGACACUGAGUUAUCCCUUUUUAGGUUUCCUCAGGUUGCCUAACUUGGUUCUAAAUUUGAAAGAGGGAUUUAAUUAAAUCUCUGGAUGAAAGAAAACUUGGGGGAGGUGGUCUGUGGGGAAGGGGUGAUAAUAAGUCAUACCUGGAAAAGUAGAAGUGGACUACUUGGCCUCUGGGAUGGACAGGGAUUCCCCAGAAAGCAAACAAUGAGGUCUCAGGGCUGGGCCUCCCUUCUCUCCAGGUGGUGGAUUGCCAGUUUAUUCCUACUCUCACUAUAGUCUUGCCUAGGUGCUUAGAAUAACCCAGAAAGAUUCUAAGCUUCUGGCCAUGUUAAGGCCUCAGAUGCAGAGAGAAAAUGCAGUAGAUUCCAGCAGAUGUGGUGUGUGGGAGAGGACAGGAAGGGUCUCUGGAAGCCCAGUGGAAAAAGAGAGGCACCAGGUGAGGCUUUGGACAGAGCAGGAAAGAAGGCAGAGAUGUGCAGUUGUCUGUUGUUUUUUUUUUUUUUUGAGAGGUAAUCUCUCAUUGUCGCCCAGGCUGGAGUGCAGUGGCACGAUCUCGCCUCAUUGCAAGCUCCGCCUCCCGGGUUCAUGCCAUUCUUCUGCCUCAGCCUCCUGAGUAGCUGGGACUACAGGCGCCCGCCACCACACCCAGCUAAUUUUUUUGUGUUUUUAGUAGAGACAGGGUUUCACUGUGUUAGCCAGGAUGGUCUCCAUCUCCUGACCUUGUGAUCCGCCUGCCUCGGCCUCCCAAAGUGCUGGGAUUACAGGUGUGAGCCACCGUGCCUGGCCAACGAUUGUCUGUUUUUAAAAACUGAGGUGAAUUUACACAUGAUAUGAAAUUAACCAUUUUAAUUAUUUAUUUAUUUAUUUUUGAGACAGGAUCUCACUCUCUCCCAGGUUGGGGUGCAGUAGCACAAUCGUAGCUCACUGCAACCUCAACCUCCUGGGCUCAAGGGAUCCUCCUGCCUCAGCCUCCCAAGUAGCUGGGACUACAGGCGUGCAUCACAGUGCCUGGCUAAUUGCCUAAUUUUUUGUAGAGACAGGGUCUUGCUAUGUUGCCCAGGCUGGUCUUGAACUCCUGGCUUCAAGUGAUCCUCCUGCCUGGGCCUCUCAAAGUGCUGGGAUUACAGGUGUGAAUCACUGUGCCCAGCCUGUAAAAUUAAAAUUUAAUUUUAUAAAAUUGAAAGGAUUUUUAAAGUAUAUAAUUCAGUGUUAUAUAGUAUAUUCACAGCAGUGUGCACUCACUGGCUCUAUCGAAUUCCAGAACACUUUCAUCACUCCAGAAGGAGACCCUACACCCAUUGGCAGUCACUCCCCAUUCUUCCCUCUCCCAGCCCCCUGGCAACAACUCAUCUACUUUCUGUUUCUAUUGAUUUACCUGUUCUGAACAUUUCAUAUUUAUAUUAAAUGGAAUCAUAUAAUGUAUGGCCUUUUGUGUCUGGUUUCUUUCACAUAACAUAGUGUUUUCAAGGUUCAACCAUGUUGUAUCAUGGAUCAGUACUUCAUUCCUUUUUUUGUGGUAAAAUAUACAUAAUAUAACAUUUACCAUUUUAAACAUUUUUAUUUUUGAAACAGGGUCUCUCUCUGUUGCUUGUGCAGUGACACCAACACAGCUUACUGCAGCCUCGAACUCCUGGGCUCAAGUGAUCCUCUUGCCUCAGCCUCCCGAGUAGCUGGGACUACAGGCACGCACCACCAUGUCUGGAUAAUUUUUGUAUUUUUUUGCAGAGAUGGGGUUUUGCCAUGUUGCCCAGGCUGGUCUUGAACUCCUGAGCUCAAGCGAUCCACCCACCUCAGCCUCCCAAAGUGUUGGGAUUACAGGCGUGAACCAUUGCACCGGCCGUCUUUUCUUUUUAAGACUGACUAAUGGUUCAUUGUAGGCAUACACCACAUUUUCUUUCUUCAUUCAUCCAUUGAUAGACGUUUAGAUGUUUCUGGGCUAGUGAAAUUUUGACUUUGGUUUGCCUCUGGAUGAGGAACAACAAAAGACAACUGAACUAGGAGGGUUUAGGGACCCAGAGACAUCAGUUGUCCCAUUUCCAAGGAUGCUGGCACGUGUGUCCUGGUCCUCAACAACCUUCUGUGAGCCUAGGGACCCAUUUCUCCUCCUUUGACAGGGACAUCAGUGGAGCCUUCUCAGACCCACAGGGGUCCUUGGUGAAUUUUGUCAUGGUUAUUUAAGGAACCUUGCCUAGAAGUCCCAACUUGCAGUUCCCCAUCGACGGGAAGGCUUGGACUCCAAGAUGAUUAUAAAGGAAUAUCGGAUUCCUCUGCCAAUGACCGUGGAGGAGUACCGCAUCGCCCAGCUGUACAUGAUACAGAAGAAGAGCCGUAACGAGACAUAUGGCGAAGGCAGCGGCGUGGAGAUCCUGGAGAACCGGCCGUACACAGAUGGCCCAGGCGGCUCUGGGCAGUACACACACAAGGUGUAUCAUGUGGGCAUGCACAUUCCCAGCUGGUUCCGCUCCAUCCUGCCCAAGGCAGCCCUGCGGGUGGUGGAGGAGUCUUGGAAUGCCUACCCCUACACCCGAACCAGGUUCACCUGUCCUUUCGUGGAGAAAUUCUCCAUCGACAUUGAAACCUUUUAUAAAACUGAUGCUGGAGAAAACCCCGACGUGUUCAACCUCUCUCCUGUGGAAAAGAACCAGCUGACAAUCGACUUCAUCGACAUUGUCAAAGACCCUGUGCCCCACAACGAGUAUAAGACAGAAGAGGACCCCAAGCUGUUCCAGUCAACCAAGACCCAGCGGGGGCCCCUGUCCGAGAACUGGAUCGAGGAGUACAAGAAGCAGGUCUUCCCCAUCAUGUGCGCAUACAAGCUCUGCAAGGUGGAGUUCCGCUACUGGGGCAUGCAGUCCAAGAUCGAGAGGUUCAUCCACGACACCGGACUACGGAGGGUGAUGGUGCGGGCUCACCGGCAGGCCUGGUGCUGGCAGGACGAGUGGUAUGGGCUGAGCAUGGAGAACAUCCGGGAGCUGGAGAAGGAGGCACAGCUCAUGCUUUCCCGUAAGAUGGCCCAGUUCAAUGAGGAUGGUGAGGAGGCCACUGAGCUCGUCAAGCACGAAGCCGUCUCGGACCAGACCUCUGGGGAGCCCCCGGAGCCCAGCAGCAGCAAUGGGGAGCCCCUAGUGGGGCGCGGCCUCAAGAAACAGUGGUCCACAUCCUCCAAGUCGUCUCGGUCGUCCAAGCGGGGAGCGAGUCCUUCCCGCCACAGCAUCUCAGAGUGGAGGAUGCAGAGUAUUGCCAGGGACUCGGAUGAGAGCUCAGAUGAUGAGUUCUUCGAUGCGCACGAGGACCUGUCCGACACAGAGGAAAUGUUCCCCAAGGACAUCACCAAGUGGAGCUCCAAUGACCUCAUGGACAAGAUCGAGAGCCCAGAGCCGGAAGACACACAAGAUGGUCUGUACCGCCAGGGUGCCCCUGAGUUCAGGGUGGCCUCCAGUGUGGAGCAGCUGAACAUCAUAGAGGACGAGGUUAGCCAGCCGCUGGCUGCACCGCCCUCCAAGAUCCACGUGCUGCUACUGGUGCUGCACGGAGGCACCAUCCUGGACACAGGCGCCGGGGACCCCAGCUCCAAGAAGGGCGAUGCUAACACCAUCGCCAACGUGUUCGACACCGUCAUGCGCGUGCACUACCCCAGCGCCCUGGGCCGCCUUGCCAUCCGCCUGGUGCCCUGCCCGCCCGUCUGCUCUGACGCCUUUGCCCUGGUCUCCAACCUCAGCCCCUACAGCCAUGACGAAGGCUGUCUGUCCAGCAGUCAGGACCACAUUCCCCUGGCUGCCCUCCCCCUGCUGGCCACCUCCUCCCCCCAGUACCAGGAGGCAGUUGCCACAGUGAUUCAGCGAGCCAACCUUGCCUAUGGGGACUUCAUCAAGUCCCAGGAGGGCAUGACCUUCAAUGGGCAGGUCUGCCUGAUUGGGGACUGCGUCGGGGGCAUCCUGGCAUUUGAUGCCCUGUGCUACAGUAACCAGCCGGUGUCUGAGAGUCAGAGCAGCAGCCGCCGGGGCAGCGUGGUCAGCAUGCAGGACAAUGACCUGCUGUCCCCGGGCAUCCUGAUGAAUGCAGCACACUGCUGCGGUGGUGGCGGUGGCGGCGGUGGCGGUGGUGGCAGCAGUGGUGGUGGUGGCAGUAGUGGUGGCUCCAGCCUGGAGAGCAGUCGGCACCUGAGCCGAAGCAACGUCGACAUCCCCCGCAGCAACGGCACUGAGGACCCCAAAAGGCAACUGCCCCGCAAGAGGAGCGACUCAUCCACCUACGAGCUGGAUACCAUCCAGCAGCACCAGGCCUUCCUGUCCAGCCUCCAUGCCAGCGUGCUGAGGACUGAGCCCUGCUCACGCCAUUCCAGCAGCUCCACCAUGCUGGAUGGCACAGGUGCCCUGGGCAGGUUUGACUUUGAGAUCACCGACCUCUUCCUCUUCGGGUGCCCGCUGGGGCUGGUCCUGGCCUUGAGGAAGACUGUCAUCCCAGCCCUGGAUGUUUUCCAGCUGCGGCCGGCCUGCCAGCAAGUCUACAACCUCUUCCACCCCGCGGACCCGUCAGCUUCACGCCUGGAGCCGCUGCUGGAACGGCGCUUUCACGCCCUGCCGCCUUUCAGCGUCCCCCGCUACCAACGCUACCCGCUGGGGGAUGGCUGCUCCACGCUGCUGGUCGAGACCGUGCAGAGAAACCCUGAGCUGGUCCUGGAGGGCGGCCCCCUGGCCCCUCUCCCCCACGGGGACGGCUUCCUGGAAACCAGUAUGCCUGUUCCCGCGCCCACCUGGCAAGACGGGCCCCGCCCGGGCUGUGCCGAGUGUGUGUACCCUCCCCUGCUCGUGGUGACGUCUGCUUCGUUGGUUGACCUGGUCCUCAGGGACACCCCCCAAUCCAUGCCCUCCUUGGCCACUCACAGUUCGUGGGACCUGGGUGCGGAUGUGCUCCAGACCCACAAUGCAGCCUUCCAAGAGCAUGGCGCCCCCUCCUCGCCGGGCACUGCCCCUGCCAGUCGUGGCUUCCGCCGAGCCAGUGAGAUCAGCAUCGCCAGCCAGGUGUCAGGCAUGGCUGAGAGCUACACGGCAUCCAGCAUCGCCCAGAAGGCCCCCGAUGCGCUCAGCCAUACCCCCAGCGUCAGGCGUCUGUCCCUGCUCGCCCUGCCCGCCCCCAGCCCCACCACCCCUGGCCCCCACCCUCCAGCCAGGAAGGCAAGCCCUGGCCUGGAGAGGGCCCCUGGCCUCCCUGAGCUGGACAUUGGAGAAGUCGCUGCAAAGUGGUGGGGCCAGAAGCGGAUCGACUACGCCCUGUACUGCCCUGACGCCCUCACGGCCUUCCCCACGGUGGCUCUGCCUCACCUCUUCCACGCCAGCUACUGGGAGUCAACAGACGUGGUCUCCUUUCUGCUGAGACAGGUCAUGAGGCAUGACAACUCCAGCAUCUUGGAGCUGGAUGGCAAGGAAGUGUCGGUGUUCACCCCCUCAAAGCCAAGGGAGAAGUGGCAGCGCAAGCGGACCCACGUGAAGCUGCGGAACGUGACGGCCAACCACCGGAUCAAUGAUGCCCUUGCCAAUGAGGACGGCCCCCAGGUUCUGACGGGCAGGUUCAUGUAUGGGCCCCUGGACAUGGUCACCCUGACUGGGGAGAAGGUGGAUGUGCACAUCAUGACCCAGCCGCCCUCAGGCGAGUGGCUCUACCUGGAUACGCUGGUGACCAACAACAGUGGGCGUGUCUCCUACACCAUCCCUGAGUCGCACCGCCUGGGCGUGGGUGUCUACCCUAUCAAGAUGGUGGUCAGGGGAGACCACACGUUUGCCGACAGCUACAUCACCGUGCUGCCCAAGGGCACAGAGUUCGUGGUCUUCAGCAUCGACGGUUCCUUUGCCGCUAGCGUGUCCAUCAUGGGCAGCGACCCCAAGGUGCGGGCCGGGGCCGUGGACGUGGUGCGGCACUGGCAGGACCUGGGCUACCUCAUCAUCUACGUGACGGGCCGGCCCGACAUGCAGAAGCAGCGGGUGGUGGCGUGGCUGGCCCAGCACAACUUCCCCCAUGGCGUGGUGUCCUUCUGUGACGGCCUGGUGCAUGACCCGCUGCGGCACAAGGCCAACUUCCUGAAGCUGCUCAUCUCCGAGCUGCACCUGCGCGUGCACGCGGCCUAUGGCUCCACCAAGGACGUGGCGGUGUACAGCGCCAUUAGCCUGUCCCCCAUGCAGAUCUACAUCGUGGGCCGGCCCACCAAGAAGCUGCAGCAGCAGUGCCAGUUCAUCACGGAUGGCUACGCGGCCCACCUGGCGCAGCUGAAGUACAGCCACCGGGCGCGGCCCGCUCGCAACACGGCCACCCGCAUGGCGCUGCGCAAGGGCAGCUUCGGCCUGCCCGGCCAGGGCGACUUUCUGCGCUCCCGGAACCACCUGCUUCGCACCAUCUCGGCCCAGCCCAGCGGGCCCAGCCACCGGCACGAGCGGACACAGAGCCAGGCGGAUGGCGAGCAGCGGGGCCAGCGCAGCAUGAGUGUGGCGGCCGGCUGCUGGGGCCGCGCCAUGACUGGCCGCCUGGAGCCGGGGGCAGCCGCGGGCCCCAAGUAGGGCACCGUGAGUGCAGCGCGGGGUCUCCAUGGUGCUAGGCCAGGGUGGCCAGCCCCGCCAGGAGGCCUGGCCUGGGCACACGCACUGACGUGGGCCUGGGAGAUUGUCCCAGGGCCUUGUGGAGGACACGGGCCGCACCACACAGUGCUCCCUGCCCUGCCUCACGUCCUCGGGCCUGACGGGUCCGGCUUGUCAUGGAAGCUGGCAGGGACCACCAGCCCCAGGAUGGCAGAGGGACCAGAACCUCCCACUCAGACUGGCCCGGGAGGUUCUCCCAGACAUUUUGCCCUGUGUGGAUCUCCAAGUGUCCUGGUGCCAGGUGUGGGCCCAGGCGCAGCCUGCCACCUCCCCAUCCACUGGCCACCCUCACUCCCAGGUCCCCUCCCAUUUGGUAGCAGCUCCAACAGGGGUCCAGCCUGCAUCUUGUUAACUCGAGUUUCUCAACUGUUCAACCUCACUGGUUUUGCACUGAUUUUUGAGAGCGGAGACCCAUUACCACCUCCUAUGGCUACAGCCCCGUUGACAUGCAUGAAACUCAGUACCUGCUGACCCAGGACCUACAACCACACUGAAGGCUCCAGUGCGGCAGAGCCUCGUGCAAGCAGGAGAGAAAGGCUGUAUCUUAAUUUCUGCACCCCGGACCCUGCCCACCUGUCUGCCUGCCCCGCCUGGAGCCCAGGCCAGUGUUGUUUCCAGCCUCAGGCCACGGGCUGGACGGGCCUGGCCGCCUCUUCCGCUCCCUGCCAUCAGUCAAGGCCGCCCGCCCACGUUUCUACGCCUUUCUACUUCUCAAUCUGAUUUCUAUGAGGUUUUUUUAAACGAGCAAUCCUUGGCUGCUUCCUUUUCUUAACUCUUUCAGUACUGAGAGCAGCCCCUCCACACUGAAAACACCCAGCACUGUGACGGAGUCCAGCCUGGUUCUGGGUCCCGUGGGCCCUGCUCCUGCCCACUUAGCGAGGCAUGGGCUCCUUGCCUCACCUGGCCCCGGCAAUCCCACUGAAUUUCUACUCUGGGGUGGGUGGGGCACACACUUCGGUUUUUUUAAUGCCAAUUCCGUUUUCAUGCCGAAUCUAAGAAGCCACAACUUGCUUUGUCAGCUUCAGGGCAGGCAGCCAUGACUUCAUUUCUCGCCUGAACAAGGACCAUGCUGUCCUGCACGCUGGGUCUGACCGUCUGCCCUCUCUCCCCAGCACCAAGCGUGACCUUGGCUGUGGCGCUCAACGGCCAGCUCCGGCGGCCCCUCUGCUGCUCCUCGGCUUUCCCGGAAGUGGGAGAGCCUGCCUGGCCUCGGCCUUUGUCCAGCGACCAGGCUCUGUCCCCGAGAAGCUACGGCCGACCUGGGUCUGGUGUUGGGACGCAUGGACCGGGCUGGGGAGGUGCACAGAGUGAUGUUAACUUUUUCCCGUGUGUAGAUAUGUACAGCCAAAGGGUCGUGUAAAUGUUCUGCAAAAGUGGGUCUAUACAGAGUGAAAGCUAUUUAUUUUGUGCAGAGAAAAAAGUCUGGAGGGAUGGAACCUUCAGGGUUUAUUCAUAUUUAAGAUGUAGCUUUUUGUUGUUUCAGGCAUUAUGUAUAAAGCAACGAUUAUUUUAUGGACCAAGUUUUCAUGUAACUGUUGCAGUGAAAGUGCAAUAUCUGACCCCCCUGCUCCCAGCAGGAAGUUGCUUGGCCCGACAAUCACAGCCCCUGUCAGGGGCCCUGUGGCCAGUGCCUCCUCCUCUCUUGGCCCCACCUUAUCCUGUCUUGCCUGCUGCCUGGGAGACCAGCCAUCCAGAGAAGCACCUGGAAGAGUCUCGGGCCCUCCUGCAAUAAAGGCCGGGAGGCCCUGUGGGCAGUGGGCUCAGCCUCUCCCCAGGGGGGCAGCUCCCCCACGGCUCCUCACUCCCCGCCUGCCUGCCCAGCCGCCAGCCAUGCCAAGGACAACAGCAAUAGUCCCCUGGGGCUCUCCCAGCGGCCCUCAGCCAUAGAUGGCAAGGUGGGCAGCCUGCCCCCCCAUGGGAAGUCUCUUCUGUAUCCAGGUCUGCUUUCCACCUCCCUUCAGAUUCCUUUUGGCACAUUCUCCUCUUGAGGAAGUACCAGUCUUUCUGAAACUAAGAGAGGGAGGGCAGCGUCCUUUAAAAAUACCAAAAAUGUUUACAGAGUUGGGUGCUGAGCUGCAGGGCUCAGGCCUGACCAGUCAUAACCAAAGGGUGAGGCAGGCCUUGCUGACUGCCACCCCCCAGGCCUGUUAGAAUAGAAGCCUUAGUCCCACUCCCACCACACCCCCACGCCCCACCACCUGCCUUCUCUUUGAUUUCUAAAGAGGGAUUCAGCAGAGACCCCCCACCCCUCCCUGGCUCGGUCUGAGUCCCACUGCCCACCCCAUCACAGCCUUCACGUCUCAGCCCCUCCCGUCUGGUCUGUCCGUGUGCCGUCUGUUUCUCUGGGCCAUGUGUGAGCAGUGUCCCCAUCUCCCCAUCCGUCCCUGCUGUCCCCGCAUCAUUGGGCCUGAGUGUGCUCUGUAUACAACGUCAUGUCUGUUACACCAAUUAAAGAAGCGGGAAGGCUUC